AGCAGUCGGGGCGGGCAGGCCCAGCUGAGAGGUGCGCGGGCGAGGACAGCGGCAGCGAUGCGGGAAUGCAUAUCAGUCCACGUGGGCCAAGCGGGAGUUCAGAUUGGCAAUGCCUGCUGGGAGCUCUUCUGCCUGGAACACGGCAUCCAGGCAGACGGCACUUUUGAUGCUCAAGCUAGCAAGAUCAACGAUGAUGACUCCUUCACCACCUUUUUCAGCGAGACUGGCAAUGGGAAGCAUGUGCCCCGGGCCGUCAUGAUAGAUCUGGAGCCUACUGUAGUGGAUGAGGUUCGGGCAGGAACCUACCGCCAGCUCUUCCAUCCAGAGCAGCUGAUCACAGGAAAGGAGGAUGCAGCCAACAACUAUGCCCGGGGCCACUACACGGUGGGCAAGGAGAGCAUUGACCUGGUGCUGGACCGCAUACGGAAGCUGACAGAUGCUUGCUCUGGCCUGCAGGGCUUCCUGAUUUUCCACAGUUUUGGUGGGGGCACUGGCUCCGGCUUCACUUCUCUGCUGAUGGAACGCCUCUCCCUGGAUUAUGGCAAGAAAUCCAAGCUGGAGUUUGCCAUCUACCCAGCCCCCCAGGUCUCUACUGCAGUGGUGGAGCCCUACAACUCCAUCCUGACCACCCACACCACACUGGAACAUUCAGAUUGUGCUUUCAUGGUGGACAACGAAGCCAUCUAUGACAUCUGCCGCAGGAACCUUGACAUUGAGCGCCCUACCUAUACCAACCUCAACCGCCUCAUCAGUCAGAUUGUGUCCUCAAUCACUGCUUCUCUCCGCUUUGACGGGGCCCUCAAUGUGGACCUCACUGAGUUCCAGACCAACCUGGUGCCCUACCCCCGCAUCCACUUCCCGCUGGUCACCUACGCGCCCAUCAUCUCUGCCGAGAAAGCCUAUCACGAACAGCUCUCUGUGGCCGAGAUAACCAGCUCCUGCUUUGAGCCCAACAGCCAGAUGGUGAAGUGCGACCCGAGACAUGGCAAGUACAUGGCCUGCUGCAUGCUCUACCGGGGCGACGUGGUGCCCAAGGAUGUGAAUGUCGCUAUUGCUGCCAUCAAGACCAAGAGGACCAUCCAGUUUGUAGACUGGUGUCCCACAGGCUUCAAGGUGGGCAUCAACUACCAGCCCCCGACCGUGGUCCCCGGGGGAGACCUGGCCAAGGUGCAGCGGGCCGUCUGCAUGCUCAGCAACACCACGGCCAUUGCGGAGGCCUGGGCCCGCCUCGACCACAAGUUCGACCUCAUGUACGCCAAGCGGGCCUUUGUGCAUUGGUAUGUGGGAGAGGGGAUGGAAGAAGGAGAAUUUUCUGAGGCCAGGGAAGACUUAGCUGCCCUGGAGAAGGAUUAUGAAGAAGUGGGGACUGAUUCGUUUGAAGAAGAAAAUGAAGGGGAGGAAUUUUAAAUAUAUACCUUCCCCUUGGCUGUGUCUCUUUAUUUAUGCUGUGCCAUUCAAAGCACAUGUUCAAGAGAACAGAACACUCUCCCCGCCCCAGCCUGAUUCCUGCCUUACCCAGGAGGAGGGUGCCUGGCCCCAGUACCCAGGGUGGCACGACUGGGCUAAGUGGACACUGAGCUUCAUCAGGCCCUCCCUGGGUAGGAGCAGCUUUGUGUCACUAAAGAAAGUGAGGGCCACUGUCUCCGGCGGGUGAGGCUGCAGCCCAGUUUCACAUGCGAGGAGGCCUAAUCAGGAGUUUCAAUUCCAGAUCGGGCUGGGUCCAGCCCCAAAACAUGGCCUGCUGGCUGGGGAGUGGGAACACUCAGAGAAAGGGGAGAUCUGGGCCUGGGAAGAUUCCGGGGCAGGGGUGAGCGGACGUUCACAUGAGUGGGUCUAUAGCCCGCUCCGGGCAUCAUCUAGACUUAGCAUGCAUUCACUCCCCCAUCACAUAUUCCAAUACACACCCUGUCCUAGGCACUGAGAGCUGGAGAGUUGGUGAUAAGCGAGACGAACACAUUUCCUGCCCUCAUACACACAUAAAUAAAGUGAAUGAGAUCAUGUCA